AUCAAUCGUCUUCCGGCGCAGCCCCGUCCCUGUUUUUUGUGCUCCUCCGAGCUCGCUGUUCGUCCGGGUUUUUUACGUUUUAAUUUCCAGGACUUGAACUGCCAUGUCCUCUGAAGAAGGAAAGCUCUUCGUGGGAGGGCUCAACUUUAACACCGACGAGCAGGCACUGGAAGACCACUUCAGCAGUUUCGGACCUAUCUCUGAGGUGGUCGUUGUCAAGGACCGGGAGACUCAGCGGUCCAGGGGUUUUGGUUUCAUCACCUUCACCAACCCAGAGCAUGCUUCAGUUGCCAUGAGAGCCAUGAACGGAGAGUCUCUGGAUGGUCGUCAGAUCCGUGUGGAUCAUGCAGGCAAGUCUGCUCGGGGAACCAGAGGAGGUGGCUUUGGGGCCCAUGGGCGUGGUCGCAGCUACUCUAGAGGUGGUGGGGACCAGGGCUAUGGGAGUGGCAGGUAUUAUGACAGUCGACCUGGAGGGUAUGGAUAUGGAUAUGGACGUUCCAGAGACUAUAAUGGCAGAAACCAGGGUGGUUAUGACCGCUACUCAGGAGGAAAUUACAGAGACAAUUAUGACAACUGAAAUGAGACAUGCACAUAAUAUAGAUACACAAGGAAUAAUUUCUGAUCCAGGAUCGUCCUUCCAAAUGGCUGUAUUUAUAAAGGUUUUUGGAGCUGCACCGAAGCAUCUUAUUUUAUAGUAUAUCAACCUUUUGUUUUUAAAUUGACCUGCCAAGGUAGCUGAAGACCUUUUAGACAGUUCCAUCUUUUUUUUUAAAUUUUUUCUGCCUAUUUAAAGACAAAUUAUGGGACGUUUGUAGAACCUGAGUAUUUUUCUUUUUACCAGUUUUUUAGUUUGAGCUCUUAGGUUUAUUGGAGCUAGCAAUAAUUGGUUCUGGCAAGUUUGGCCAGACUGACUUCAAAAAAUUAAUGUGUAUCCAGGGACAUUUUAAAAACCUGUACACAGUGUUUAUUGUGGUUAGGAAGCAAUUUCCCAAUGUACCUAUAAGAAAUGUGCAUCAAGCCAGCCUGACCAACAUGGUGAAACCCCAUCUGUACUAAACAUAAAAAAAUUAGCCUGGCAUGGUGGUGUACGCCUGUAAUCCCAGUGACUUGGGAGGCUGAGGCAGGAGAAUCGCUUGAACCCGGGAGGCGGAGGUUGCAGUGAGCUAAGAUCGCGCCACUGUACUCCAGCCUGGGCAACAGCGAGACUCCAUCUCAAAAAAAAAGGAAAUGUGUAUCAAGAACAUGAUUAUCCAGCGGUAUUUUCUAAUUCAGAUCAUCAAACUGAUUAUAUAGAAGAGUUGGCUUUAAAAUGUUUGCAAAUGUCUUUUUUUUUUUAAUACUGGAAGAAAAAAUAUUCUGUUGUGUCUCAUACAGUGCUUAGGAUGUCUUUCACAGAGCUUAUUAAAAAGAUGAAACCUGAGAACAAACUGCUUUAUUCUUACUCAGCCCAUUUUGCAAAUUAAAAGUGGGGGCAGAGGUGGGCGGAUCACCUGAGGUCAGGAGUUCGAGACCAGCCUGGCCAACAGGGCAAAACCCCAUCUCUACUAAAAAUACAAAAGUUAGCGGGGCGUGGUGGCGGGUGCAUGUAAUCCCAGCUACUCGGGAGGCUGAGGCAGGAGAAUUGCUUGAACCCAGGAGGCGGAAGUUGCAGUGAGCUGAGAUUGUGCCACUGCACUCCAGCCUAGGUGACAGCAAGACUCUGUCUCAAAAAAAAAAAAAUGGCACAUCAACGAGAGGGAGGCUUGGAGAAUAUUUGGUUGGUGGGUGGGCAGGGACUGCCAGAGGGUUAGGUGUACAUUGAGGCCUGAGGCCUGCUGGAAUUGGGUUUCCUUAACUGGUCUCUUAUCUUAGUCCCAUUGUUCUGAGAACAUAAGCACCUAAUCUCAUGGCGUGAGCUAAUCCCUAUCAUAAAUAGUGGUACCAGUUCAUUCCUUCCCCUGAAAUGAUGGGGGUUGGGCAGAGAUGCACUGAACUCAUCUUUGUGUAUGAGGGCCAUGAGAGAGGCCUGGUUUGAAAACAAUGCUAAGAGCUCAGAUUCCAGGAUUUAUGUAGGGGCUCUUCUACUUCCCAGGUAUUUGACCUCAGGUGAGUCAUUUAAUUUCAGCCUUAUGCCAUUUUACAUUUUCUGUGGAGGGUUAGGUUAAUUGGCAUAUAAAGCCACUGAGAAGAGUUGGCAAAGCUCUCAGUCACGGGGAUUUGAUCUUUUUUGGUGUGUGUGUGUCUUGGGUGGUAAAGUGGUAAUUUUGUAAUUCUAGCUGGUCUUAGUUCCUCAGUUCUGCUCCCUUUAGUCAUGGUUCUUUCUAGUGGCUGUAUUGAGGCCCCAUGGGUGUUAUCCCUCCAUUGGUUCUAGUUUGGAACAGAAAAAUCUGUUGUAUUCAUGGCUUUCACCUGGCUAAUACUGAGCUAAGUUACCACCAGGUUGCAAACUCCAGGACAUUAUUGUCCUGAGCUGCCUAUUCCCUUGCUGGUGCGUUGUGGAACCCUGUAUUAUUAGUUCCAGUCCUGGAGGCCUGCCUCCUGAGUUUCCCAGCUAGUUGGGACAGGCCCCAAUAUCCCUUCUUCCUGUAACCCAAACAGUCAUGAAUUUGCUUUGGCAGGUGGAUGGAGACUUGGGAACUUCCACCUCACCCACUAAGCCAGGCCCAGGCUAUGGGGCAUUGUGGCUAACCCCACCAGGUGGAUACUUGGUCUGAGGACGCAUCUUAUUCUGGGCCUUUAGGGAGCUAAGGCAGUGAGAAUUGGCAGGAGGACUGCUGUGAAUGCCUUGUAGGUCGGGGGAUUGGAGGGGGUCCUCUGCUCCCUGUCUCUCAGGAUGGCAAUGUACCUCUCACCCCCAGUGUCAGCUGAGGUAGGAUCCAUAAUCAGUAAUAUUCCUGCAACAAAAUGUUCCUAAGUGGAAUCAAUGAAGACCAAAAUUUAUUUGUAUAACAACUCUAAACCUGCUCUGCUCUGCUGUGUUUACAAUGUGCUUUGUGAUCAUCCAGCCCAGGGAGUCCCAGUCUCUGGCUGUCUAUCUGCUCUAAGGAAGAGAGCCCACAGUUCUCUAUAGUGCCAUAGUCUGUGAUGAAUAAAGUUCCAGAUUUGAGGUCAACCCCCGACCACCCUUAAAGUGCUUGUUGGUCUCCUACUUUGGUUUGUCUUCAGCAUCCAACUGAUGCACAUUUGUCAAGAACCCACUGAGGCUAGAAACCCCCCAAACACUCAAGGUACCUUGAGAACAUGUAUCCCAAGACCUGCAAAGACCAAACACAUGGCCUGUAACUACUUUUCACUUUCAAGCCCUGGAACUUGUCUGUACCAAAAAUCUUUCUGAACCAUUCACCAAAUCUCUUGUCAAGGGCCAGAAUAAAUUAAGAGAUUGGCUUUUGGUUUUCAAUUAGGCUUUCAAGUCCUAAGCCCAACCCCUCCUAUCCCACCUAGGCAGAAAUCACUUCAGAUCCUUGCUUCCUAGUUUAAUUUCUUCUCUGCCUCAGUUAUAACAUCCAUAAAAUGGAAAUAAUAAUACCCACCUCACACAGGGGUUAGGAGUGUUUUUUUGUUGGUUUUUUUCCAGACAGGGUCUCACUCUGUCUCCCAGGCUGGAGUGCAGUGGCACAAUCUCGGCUCACUGUACCCUCCGCCUCCCAGGUUCAAGCAGUUCUCAUGCCUCAGCCUCCCAAGUAGCUGGGAUUACAGGUGCCUGCCACCACGCCCGGCUAAUUUUUGUAUUAAUAGAGACAGGGUUUCACCGUGUUGGGCAGGCUGGUCCUGAACUCCUGACCUCAAGUGAUCCACCCGCCUCGGCCUCCCAAAGUGCUGGGAUUACAGGCGUGAGCCACCACACCUGGCCUAGGAGUUAAGAGUAUUAAAUGUUAAGAACAGACCAAGUCCAUCAAACAGCUCCACACCCUUGUUCCAUGUUCUGGAUUGGGGAGUUGUGGGGGUGGAGGUGUAGAACUUUUAAAAAGCUUCUUAAAAUAAGUUGCUGUGAAUACUUCAGGUAUAUAAAAAAACAUUGGUUGACAAUAAGCCAGUGUUCUGCCAUUCUUACCUGCUUAUCAAGACAAAACCUGCUCAAGUCCCUGCCCAGCUGCAUUCCAAGUGUUUUCAAGUUUGGUGGUAAGACCUGACCUGAGGCUUCUUAUAACCUUUACUCAGUGGGAAUAUGCAUACAGUUCACUACAGAAAUAUUUGUAUUUACUUAGAGGAAGUGCCCUGGAUCUGGGGGCGGGGGGGGGCGGGGGGAAUGGGUCUUUUCUAAAUUGUUAAAAGCAGUUCAUGCCAUUAUUCUUAAUAAACAUUUCUAAUAUGCUGUGAAA